AGAUCCUCUAAGACAAGACAGGGAUAAAGUCUCCCGUGGAAUCCCCUCCCGCCUCAUAUUCCCUGACCCUGCCCUCCCUGCGAGAACUCCAGUCCGGGCUCCACAAAGGGCGCGGUAAGAAACGUACACUUCCGAGGGGCAGACAAGGAGGGGGCGUUCACCUACACCCCGGCCGGGCUAUGGUCGGGAACAGGGUGAGGGGCCCAAGCCCCGGCUGCGGCAGGCGGGCGCCCUUACCCAUGCUGACUCUGGAGCGGGCCGGGUGGCGCUGCCCAUCCCCGGAUCCUUCGUAGAUGGAGUCUUGCUUAGUCGCCCAAGCUGGAGUAGUGUGGCUCGAUCUCAGCUCUGCAACCUCUGCCUCCCAGGGUUCAAGCAAUUCUCCUGCCUCAGUUUCCAGAGUAGCUGGAAUUAUAGUGCAGAUUCUGGGAAAGUGAACUCCACGGAAGACUCAGAAACCAAGUUCUAAUUCAGUUGCCAUGAAAACUUAAGGUGAGAGGAUUGUCAACCAGUGAAAAAUACGGAGGAAAACACUAACAGAAUAUGAUGAAGAAGCCAAGACUUGGGCUGCUUGCAUUACAUUAACCGAGGUUUACCCGCAGCGAGGCUGCCUCCAAAGCAUCCGGAGUUUGCAACCAUCACUGUCCACCCCGCGAGCUGCGAUAGUGCGAGAACUACAAUUCCCGUGGGGCUGUGCGGGAGCAUCGCGAGAGUUACAUUAACUGUGGCGGCGGGAAGGCGGAGCCUGCAGCUGGCUGGGCGGUUAGGAGGGCCCGGGGCCGAGACGAUGGCUGACCACAACCCUGACAGCGACUCCACGCCGCGCACGCUGCUGCGACGCGUGCUGGAUACAGCGGACCCGCGCACCCCGCGGCGACCCCGGAGUGCUCGGGCUGGAGCCCGGAGAGCCCUGCUUGAAACGGCUUCCCCCAGGAAGUUGAGUGGCCAAACAAGGACGAUAGCCAGAGGGCGUUCCCAUGGAGCCAGGUCUGUUGGCAGAUCGGCCCAUAUUCAGGCCAGUGGGCACUUGGAGGAACAGACACCUCGGACGCUGCUGAAGAACAUCCUACUAACUGCCCCAGAAUCUUCCAUCCUGAUGCCUGAGUCGGUAGUGAAGCCAGUGCCAGCACCGCAGGCGGUCCAACCCUCCAGACAAGAGAGCAGUUGCGGCAGCCUGGAGCUGCAACUUCCUGAGCUCGAGCCCCCCACAACCCUGGCUCCAGGUCUGCUGGCCCCUGGCAGGAGGAAACAGAGGCUGAGACUGUCAGUGUUUCAGCAGGGAGUGGACCAGGGGCUGUCUCUCUCCCAAGAGCCUCAAGGGAAUGCUGAUGCCUCUUCCCUCACCAGAUCCCUCAACCUGACCUUUGCCACACCUCUUCAGCCACAGUCAGUGCAGAGGCCUGGCUUGGCCCGCAGACCUCCAGCCCGCCGAGCUGUAGACGUGGGUGCCUUUUUGCGGGAUCUGCGAGAUACUUCCCUGGCUCCUCCAAACAUUGUGUUGGAGGACACCCAGCCGUUCUCUCAGCCCAUGGUUGGCUCCCCCAACGUGUAUCACUCCCUGCCCUGCACGCCUCACACUGGGGCUGAAGACGCUGAGCAGGCUGCCGGUCGCAAGACACAGAGCAGUGGGCCUGGGCUGCAGAAGAAUAGCCCUGGGAAACCAGCCCAGUUUCUGGCAGGAGAGGCAGAGGAGGUCAAUGCCUUUGCUCUGGGCUUCCUGAGCACCAGCAGUGGUGUCUCUGGAGAAGAUGAAGUAGAGCCCUUACACGAUGGAGUUGAAGAGGCAGAGAAAAAGAUGGAAGAAGAAGGUGUGAGUGUGAGUGAAAUGGAGGCAACAGGAGCACAAGGACCCAGCAGGGUAGAAGAGGCUGAGGGACACACAGAGGUGACAGAAGCAGAGGGAUCCCAGGGGACUGCUGAGGCUGACGGGCCAGGAGCAUCUUCAGGGGAUGAGGAUGCCUCUGGCAGGGCAGCAAGUCCAGAGUCGGCCUCCAGCACCCCUGAGUCUCUCCAGGCCAGGCGACAUCAUCAGUUUCUUGAGCCAGCCCCAGCGCCUGGUGCUGCAGUCUUAUCUUCAGAGCCUGCAGAGCCUCUGUUGGUCAGGCAUCCCCCUAGGCCCCGGACCACCGGCCCCAGGCCCCGGCAAGAUCCCCACAAGGCUGGACUGAGCCACUAUGUGAAACUCUUUAGCUUCUAUGCCAAGAUGCCCAUGGAGAGGAAGGCUCUUGAGAUGGUGGAGAAGUGCCUAGAUAAAUAUUUCCAGCAUCUUUGUGAUGAUCUGGAGGUAUUUGCUGCUCAUGCUGGCCGCAAGACUGUGAAGCCAGAGGACCUGGAGCUGCUGAUGCGGCGGCAGGGCCUGGUCACUGACCAAGUCUCACUGCACGUGCUAGUGGAGCGGCACCUGCCCCUGGAGUACCGGCAGCUGCUCAUCCCCUGUGCAUACAGUGGCAACUCUGUCUUCCCUGCCCAGUAGUGGCCAGGCUUCAACACUUUCCCUGUCCCCACCUGGGGACUCUUGCCCCCACAUAUUUCUCCAGGUCUCCUCCCCACCCCCCCAGCAUCAAUAAAGUGUCAUAAACAGAA